GCGGAGGAGCGGCCCCAGCCAGAAGACAGGGCACCCGCGGCCUUGCUGCGCAUGCUCGCGCUGUGACCCCGGCUUGAGGUAACAGCGCGAGCUGAGGCUGGGGCCCUUGGCGCGGAGGCUGAGGGACCCGCCGCGGCGCUGUCGCCGGAGAGGGAGGGCACCGCUGUCGCCAGAAGCCAAGGAGUCCUCAGUGACGGUGGGAUCCACAACAUCUCCACAUCGCUGUCCCCACCCAGCCAGGGCAGCGCCAGCACUAGCUCAGACGCAAGGACGGAACCGCUGGACUCCAGGUUCCUUGCCUGGGAGUAGGAGAAAUCCACCUGCUGGGGGCUGAGUGUGGCCUGAGGGACAGGCCCUGGGUCCCGGGAUGCCCCUGCCCGAGCCCAGCGAGCAGGAGGGUGAGAGUGUGAAGGCCAGCCAGGAGCCAUCCCCCAAGCCAGGCACAGAAGUCAUCCCGGCAGCCCCCAGGAAGCCCAGAAAGUUCUCCAAACUGGUCCUGCUCACAGCCUCCAAAGACAGCACCAAGGUGGCGGGGGCCAAGCGCAAGGGUGUGCACUGUGUCAUGUCCCUGGGGGUGCCCGGCCCCGCCACCCUUGCCAAGGCCCUCCUCCAGACCCACCCCGAGGCCCAGCGGGCCAUUGAGGCAGCCCCUCAGGAGCCUGAGCAGAAACGGAGCAGGCAGGACCCAGGCACAGACAGAACAGAAGACAGUGGAUUAGCAGCGGGGCCUCCUGAGGCUGCUGGGGAGAACUUUGCCCCCUGCUCUGUGGCGCCCGGCAAGUCCCUGUAACCUUGACAACAGGCGCAUCCUCCCAGGCCACCAACCCAGCCAUAGGCUCUUCUCUGUCCGCAGGGCUUCUGGGGCCAAAUGGGUGAAUCUUUGCUUUUAACAUUGUGUGAUUUCUUUUCUUUUUUUUUUUUUUUUUAGAUCAAGUAUAAGUUACUUUUGUAAGCAGAAAAAUACUUUCAAACAAGAAUAAAAGAAGCUGUUCGCUAGACCCCAUAAUGGGCAGGUUUUAAACA